UUUUUUUUUUUUUUUUUUUUUUGAGAUGGAGUCUCGCUCUGUCGCCCAGGCUGGAGUGCAGUGGUGCGAUCUCCGCUCACUGCAAGCUCCGCCUCCUGGGUUCAUGCCACUCCCCUGCCUCAGCCUCCCGGGUAGCUGGGACUACAGGCGCCCACCACCAUGCCCGGCUAAUUUUUUGUAUUUUUAGUAGAGACGGGGUUUCACCAUGUUAGCCAGGAUGGUCUCGAUCUCCUGACCUUGUGAUCCACCCACCUCGGCCUCCCAAAGUGCUGGGAUUACAGACGUGAGUCACUGCACCCGGCCAAAUGUUUUCUCUUUCUACCAGUUGUAGUUACAUGGUUACUUACAUUGUGAGAUGAAUUCUGCCAUUAACGGGAGAUCAGCUCUACCCAAUAAUCAAGUGACUUCUGUAUACUUGAUACGUUUAUUAUGUGUUGUUUCAUGUGAGCUUUUAUUUUCCCAACUGUGGCAGGGACUGGCUGGCUACUUCCAGCCCAUUUCUCUUUCCUCUUGGAAACACAGCUGGACUCCCUUUCCUGCCUAGUUAGCUGGUCCCAUGUCACUGAACUCUGGCCAAAGAGGGAGAGCCAAAAGUCUGUAUGCCACAUCUAGCCCUGCGCCUAACCUCUCCUGCAGGCACCUGCUCAUCUCUUCCGCCUUGCUGGUUAGAUGGCCAUGACUAGGGCAGUCUUGGAAACUGCUUGUUAAAGAUGCCAAAGCUUCCGUCAGCCUGGUGUCCUGAAUGAAUGUAUGGAACAGAGCCCCUCCCCUUCCAUUAUCAAAUGGACUCUAUAUAAACUAUUGUUAAGCAGUUCCGUUUGCAAGGUUAAUCUUUUAUGAUAGCUGGUGUUUCCUUAACUGAUUUCUCAUCCUAAUUGCUCUUCAUUCUGGAAGCCUUCUUACUAAUUCUCUUUGCAAGUGGCAUUAUUUGCUUUUGAAGUGUUACUGCUUAUAUUUUGAAGCCAUCAUUUGCCAAUAUUGGAGUAUAAUGUGAUCUUUUUUCAAGUAAUUCUGCUCUUCUUAACAAUAAUGUAAUGAGACCAUUUAGGUGCUUUUGCAGUCCAGUGGGUAGGCUGCCUUCAUAGUUUGUCACAUGUGAAUGACUCAUCUCAUAGUGCAUUGCUUCACAGCACAGACUGCUGCGUGGGAGAAGUCUGCAGGCCCUCCAGUCCCCGGAAAGGCUCAUCUCCUCAACCACAGACAGAGGCCAGAAUACAUAACCUUUGAUCAUGGGCGUGUAGUCCUUCUGUGUGUUGCUGGGUUUGAUUUGCGACUGUUUUGUUAAGGCUUUUUUUGCAUCUGUUUUUAAAGGAUGUAUUGGACUGGGCGUGGUGGCUCACACCUGUAGUCCCAGCACUUUGGGAGGCUGAGGUGGGUGGAUCACUUGAGGUCAGGAGUUUGAGACUAGCCUUGCCAACAUGGCAAAACCCCGUCUCUACUAAAAAAAAUACACACACACACACACACACACACACACACACACACACACUAGCCAGUCAUGGUGGCACAGGCCUAUAAUUCUAGCUACUCAGGACACUGAGGCAGGAGAAUCACUUGAACCUGGGAGGCAUAGGUUGCAGUGAGCCGAGAUUGUGCUAAUGCACUCCAGGCUGGGUGACGAGAGUGAAACUCCAUCUCAAAAAAAAAAAAAAAAAAAAAAAAAAAACAUGUAUUGACUUAUAGUUUUGGUUUUGCUUUUUCUUGUGUUAUUUUUGUUUUGGUGUCAGGGUAAUACUGGCCUUAGUGGAAUGAGUUAAGAAGUGUUCUUUCUUCUAUGUUUUGGAAGAGUUUGUGAAGAAUUAUUAUUAAUUCUUUGUUAAGCGUUUGAUAGAAUUCGCCCAUGAAACCCUGUGGGACUGGACUUUACUCUGAUUUUUAAAAAAUUACUAAUUCAGUUUCUUUACUUGUUACAGGAUUAUUCAGAUUAUCUAUUUCUUUCCAAGUCAGUUUUGGUAGUUUGUGUCUUUUUCAUAAUUUGUCCACUUUAUCUAGGUUAUCUAAUCCACUUUAUCUAGGUUAUCUAAUCUGCGGCCGUGCAGUUGUUUUUAGGAUUUCCUUACAGUCCUUUUUAUUUCUGUCAGGUUGGUAGUAAUGUAACCUCCUUUGUUCCUGAUUUUAGUAAUUGAACUCUUCUCUCUUUUUUUCUUGGUCAGUCUAGCUUAAAGGUUUGUCAAUCUUGUUGAUCUUUUAAAAUAACCAGCUUUUGGUUUUAAUGAUUUUUCUCACUUGUUUUUCUGUUCUUUAUUUCAUUUAUUGGUUUCUGUUUUUAUUGUUUUCUUCCUUCCACUUAUUUUCUGUUCAGUUUAGUCUUCUUUUUGUAGUUUAAGGUGGAAAGUUAGAUUAUUUACUUGAGGGUCUUUUUUAGUACAGGUGUUCAUAACUACAAAUUUCCAUCUAAGUACUGCUUUUGCUGUAUUUCAUGAGGUUUGGCCAUACAUCUCAAAAUUAUUUUCUAAUUUCCCUUGUGAUAUCUUCUUUGAUUCAUUGCUUAUUUAUUUUUAGUUUUUAUUUUUAUUUUUAUUUUAUUUUUGUAGAGACAGGGUCUUGCUUUGUUACCCAGGCUGGAGUGCAGUGACAUGAUUAUAGUUCACUAUGAUGAUCACUGUAACUUUGAACCCCUGGGCUCAAGCAGUUCUCUUGCCUCAGCCUCCCAGGUAGCUAGCAAUACAGGCAUACACCACCACACCUGGGUAAUUUUUAAAUUUUGUUGUAGAGACAGGCUGUGUCUGUUGCUGUGUUGCCCAGGCUGGUCUUGACCACCUGGCCUCACGUGAUCCUCCCACCUUAGCCUCCCAAAGCACUGGGAUUACAGGUGUGAGCCACCUUAUCUGGCCUGAUUCAUUGUUUAUUAAUGAAUAUGAAUUUCCUCAUAUUUAUACAUUUUCUAAAUUUCCUUCUGUUAUUGAUUUCUAAUUUCAUUCCAUUGUAGUUGGAGAACAUACUUUAUAUGAUUUCUAUCCUUUGAAGUUUAUUCACAUUUGUGAAAAAUGUCCUAACAUACUGGGUAUCCUUGAGAAUAUUCUGUAUGCACUUGAGGAAAAUCUACAUUCUGCUCCUGUUGAGUGGAAUGUUCCAUAGAUUUUGUUCUAGGUCUGCAGCAUUGUUCAAAUCUUCUUUUUUUGUUCAUCUUCUAUCUAGUUGUCCUAUCCAUUAUUGAAUGUGGAGUACUGAAGUUUGUCACUAUUUCUCUGUUUUUCCUUCUAUUCUGUCAGAUUUUGAUUCAUGUAUUUGAAGUUCUGCUGUUAGAUGUAAUAUAUUUAUGUUUGCUUGGCAGAUUGGCCCUUUUAUCAUUAUAAACUGUCUUCAGCCAUGCACCUCUCUUUUGGUUACUGUUUGCACCUUUUUUCUGUUGUCAUACUUUCUACCUAUUUGUGUCUUUGAACACGAAGUGUGUGUCUUGUAGACAGCAUGUAAUUGCAUCAUGAUUUUUCAUUCAUUCUGUCAAUCUGCUUGUUUAAAAAAUCAGCUUUAGUUAGGAAAAUUCACAUCCAGCAAAAUGUAUCCAUUUAAAAUCUUAGCAGGUAUGUACACUUGCUAAUUAUUAUUAUUCUCCCCAUCCAGAUGAGCUCCCUUUGCCCUGUUACCCUGCCUGAUCAGCUUUACAGCCCUACAUCAGUCUCUCCAGUGUCUCUUCUCUCAUACCUGGCUGUAGAGUUCCAACUCAGAAGGCCACACAAGCAUCUGACUGCAGCUCUGUGAAUCAGUAGAGUUCACUGUGUAACCCACAGUGUUCCCGUUGACUAGGCCCAUUCCUGAAGGCAGCUUAUUCCAGCUUUCUCAGUGUUUCUCCUGUCUGCCUUUACCACCUGUUCAUUAACUCUUAGCCAUCAACCCUCCCCUCAACCCCGCCACUUUCAGCUACAGCUCCAUUGCCUUCUUCCUAUAGGCGUUGAAACGUGUCUCUACCCAGUCACCAAAGACCACCCCCAACCCCCAGUGACCCAGCACACCUAUCUAGCUACCAUCCCGUCUCUGUCCUUUGCUUUGCAGCCAAACCUUUUGAAUGAGAUGUUUUUCGUCAUGACCUCACCCUACAUCCCCUUUCUCUGUGAAAUUUAAAUGGUGUUUCUCAGGAUUCUGUCCUAAGCACACCUACAUUUGUGAUGUACAUGUUCUUCCUGGGAAACUGUAACUUCAUUCAUGGCUUUAUAUCAUCUGAUUAUACACCAGAGCCUGAUGGGAGGUAGGUGGCACACUCAAAAGGUUCCAUCGAUCUCUGCCUGUUGAUUGGAGCCUUUAAUCCAUUUCUAUUUAAUGUAAUUACUGAUAAGGCAGAAUUUACAUCUGCAAUUUUGCUGUUUGUGUUCUGUGUGUCUUGUGAUAUUUUUGUGUCUUUGUUGCUCCAUUACUGCCUUCUUUUGUUUUAAAUAUUUUCUAAUGUGGUGUUUUAAUUCCCCAUCAUUUCUAUUAUAAUGUACUUAAAAAACUAUUUUGUUAGUGAUUGCCGCAGGGAUUUUAACUAACACAGCUCACUCUUAGCUAGGUUUAGUGUUUUUGUUGAAUAAAUGCUCCUGGAAUUCUUUCAAGUCCGGUUAUUUUCCAGAGUUCUGAAACAGUUGCUUUUGGCAAUUUUCACUAGUCUUCUCAUUGCAGUUACACAGAAGUAUAUUUUCAGAGGUUUUUAUACUGCCAUCCCUGCUUACUUCACCUACUUAUUUAUGAUUUAUUUGUCCUGUUUUACAAAUGUGUAUCCAGUGUAAUGAAUAACAAAAUGCUUUAAUUUGGGAGAUGCUAUUGUAUUAAUUGCCCUUUUAACAGUUGUGAUAGAAAUAUGUGGAAGAUACUAUUCCAAAUAUGAAAACAGUUUUGGGUAAUUAAUUAAGUGGAAAAGAUUAUAUAGAUUGUGUUAGAAGAUAAAUUAUGAACAAAGUCAAGCACUUUAAAGCUGAAAGGUGUUUAGAAAUGUCCACUUUUCAGAAGAGGAAUCUGAGGGCUGGAGAAUGUAAAUACCUUGCUUAACAUUAUAUGACUAUUAGCAAUUUUAUGGGUUUGUUUGUGUUUGUUUGUUUGUUUGUUUGUUUUUUCUCUUUUUGGAGGAGGUCUCGCUUUGUCACCCAGGCUGGAGUGCAGUGGCGCGAUCUCGGCUCACUGCAACCUCUGCCUCCUGGGUUCCAGCGAUUCUCCUGCCUCAGCCUCCUGAGUAGCUGGGACUCCAGGCACGCCACCACUCCUGGCUGAUUUUUGUAUUUUUAGUAGAGAUGGGGUUUUACCACGUUGGCCAGGCUGGUCUUGUACUUCUGACCUCAAGCGAUCCACCUGCCUUGGCCUCCCAAAGUGCUGGGGUUAUAGGUGUAAACCACUGAGCCCGGCCACUAAUAGCAAUUUUGGAAAUUCUUCCUCAGCCUCUUAAUGUUUCACUGCAUCAUUUUUAAGCCAUAGUAAGACAGAAAAACGUAAAUGGAAUAUUAGAACAUGACUCAAAUGAGAUAAUCUAUUGUGUUAACCUUGGAUAAAUAACACUUUCAAAUUGAUGAUGUUUUAAAACAUUUCUCUCUAAUUUUGUCUUACAUUCCAUGUUGUAGGGAGAAUCACUCUUCAUAGUGGAGUAAUAAUAUUUUGAAGGUCGUGGAUCCCUUUGAGAAUCUUAAGAAUUAUCACCUCUUUCCUCAGAAAAAUGUAUACACUGCACAGGCAUGCUGGAUUUUUUAUUGUUUGCAUAUCCCUGGAGGAUUAUUGAUGGGUUCAAGUUAGGGCCCUGCUGUAGUUUGUUUUAAUCUAUGCUUCUAUUUUCAUCCUCAGUUUUAUUUUUUCUGUCAAAUUUAAAUUGUUAAAAUAAUAGUUACUCAAAUGCAGAUAUUAAGAAGUCAGGGCUGGGCACGGUGGCUCACGCUUGUAAUCCCAGCACUUUGGGAGGCCGAGAUGGGUGGAUCACGAGGUCAGGAGAUCGAGACCAUCCUGGCUAACAUGGUGAAACGCCAUCUCUAGAAAAAUACAAAAAAUUUGCCGGCGUGGUGGCGGGCGCCUAUAGUCCCAGGUACUUGGGAGGCUGAGGCAGGAGAAUGGCGUGAACCCGGGAGGCGGAGCUUGCAGUGAGCCGAGUUCGCACCACUGCACUCCAGCCUGGGUGACAGAGCGAGACUCCGUCUCAAAAAAAAAGAAGUCAGAUUGUUUUUUCAUGCUAUUUUUCUUCUUAUAAAAUAGACCAAAUAGCUUUCAAGCUAUAUAAAAUUUGUGUUAUAAUAUUGCUUUCAAUCAAGAAUUCUUAGCUUUAGAAAUUCUGUUUAUGUGAUUUUUAAGUAAUUAAAGUUAUCUUAUUGCCUAGUUGUUUUCAGUAGACUACAAAUGUACUGAAUUUUUGUAUCUACUAACAGUUUUAAUACUAUUUUAUUGCUUUUUAGUUUCAGUUUGAAAAAAUCUGAUAAUACACUGUUUAUUAUAAUUACAAUAUUUUAAAUCUUAGGUAUGAUGGAAGUCCUAAGUGUUAAUAUAUGCAGCAUAUCCCAGCUUGAACACUGGCAGCUGGGUGCUUGUCAGUACAGCAUGGUGGGUUGCUCAUGGCAUCGUAUUGACUGUGUAUUAACACAGAAUAUUCUGUUGGGCUGUGAGCUGAUUGUUUAGAAUGUAAAUGAAGCUGCUGAUGGAUCUGGUGACUGAUGGCUUAAAUUCCAAUUAAUCAAUUACUUCAUCACUUUCUUAAUUCAGAUCAAAUAUCUCCAGAGUGCACACAAUUCUUUUAGUGGUAUUAAGAGAAAUUAAUGCUUUAGAACUAAUUUUCAUCAAUCUCUUAUAAAUGUCAAUAUCUUUUUCACUUGUCUCCUAAGUGAUGACAUUAUACUUUAAGUGUUUGGGACAUAUUAUAGUACCUCAGCUGUCUGUCACUUGUUAGUGGGACGGGGUGGUGGUUAAAUGACACUGUACUCAUCCACAUGGUCUCUGUAGUGCUAUUCGUCUUGCUACCAGCUUGAAAAUUUCAUGCAGAGUCAUUAAAUCGUAUGAAUGAUUUAAAAAUUAAGUUUAAUGGCAGACAAUCUGGUAUUAUAAAUGCAAAGUCAAUGCCUAUCUUUCUUUUGUUGGCCGUAUACCCUAGCCGAUCUCUUUCAGAGCUGUUGGAUUUGUGAGCUGUUGUAGGAAGUCUACUAAUAUUACAGGGUAACUUAUUAUGCGAUAUGACAGACUCGUGCUCCGACGGUGUCCUGUCAGUUUCUUCAGCACACUUGAUGCACCCUCCUAUGUGACACAUACACGAGUUGAUCUUAAUUGUCAUUAAGCCUGUUGACUCUUGUCAGUUGUAUAAAAUAAAAUCAAGUAUUCAUAAGCAGUCUGUAAUAGGAUAUAAGCAGGCCAACUUAGUAAUACAUUUUUUGCUGAGCCUUAACUGGCGUCAGUUUUAGCGAGUGCUUUCUGUUAAAAAAUUAUUAGAUGCAGUUCUUGUGAAAUAAGUCAAGCUGGCCAUCUUUCUGAUUUGCUAGAGUUCAUUCUUUCUCUCUUUAAAUCACCUCAGUUAUUGAAAGGUUAGUAUUUUUAACUGUACUUAACUUGAGUAAAAGUAAUAACGUUGUUUUUCUCUAAGUUUAAAAAAUAGCAUAUGAUUUAACAUGAGGCAUGGCUUUUUUCUUUAAACAAAGUCAGCUAUUUUUUCAGUGUUUAAUAAGUUUACAGAAAUUUAGAUAUUUGUUUCACUUUUAGAAACACAGAAUACAGGAAAUUUAUGAGACUCCAGAGAUUCUCACUUGUUUUUUUCUUUAUGUAAUAGAAAAUCUAGAGUAGAGUGAAUGGCAUUGACAUCUCACAGAUGUGUCAGAUAGAGUCUAGAAUUUAGUCCAUUUUACGUUACUUUAAUAUUUUAUAUCAGAACAUUCACCCAUAUAUAAAGGGGGAAAUUCAAUCUAGAAAAAAACUGUAACUUUAAAAUAAUAUGCACUGCAACCUUUCUUGUACUGCUUCUUAGUUGAAACCAGUGAGCUCGUGCAAUAUAUUUUUUUAUAAUUCUUUUGACAAAUAACCCCUAACGGUUUAUUUAAAUAUAUGUAUGCGUGUGUGUAUAUAUAUAUGCGUGUAUAAUAUAAUAUAUGUCUCUAAAAUCUCUAAAAUUAACCUCAAUUGUUUAGUUAUUUACCUUUAGGAAUAGUUGUUUUAAUAUUUUUAUAUUUUAUUUUCAUAUUUUAUUUUAUACACACACACACACACACACACACACACACACACACAGGGGGAGACAGAGACAGACAGACAGACAGAGACAGAAAAGGUCUCGCACUGUCCCAGGCUAGAGUGCUGUGGCUUAAUCAUAGCUCACUGCAGUCUCGAACUCCUGGGCUCAAGUGAUCCUUCCACCUCAGUUUCCCGAGUAGCUGGGACUACAGGUGCUUGCUACCAUGCCCCACUAAUUUUUUAUUUUUUAGUUUUUGUAGAGAUGGGGUUUUCUCGUGUUGCCCAAGCUGGUCUUGCACUUCUGGGUCCAAGCCAUUCUCACGUCUUGGUCUCCUAAAGAGUUGAGGUUACAGACGUGAGUCACUGUGCCCAGCCCUAUAUUUUUUAAAGUAUAUGUAAUCAGAUGACAUUGUCUCAGAUAUACUUUAAUUGAUAACGCCAAUAACUGGAGAAUCUUUUCAUGGCUCUUGAUCUUUUUGUGCCUUAGACAGGUGGGUUCAUGUCUCUGUAUUUCCCAGAUUCCAUUUUAACAAUGAUAAUUCCCAUAUUACAGGGUACUUAAAAGGAUUAAAAAUAAAAUUGGUGACUGGGCAUGGUGGCUCAUGCCUGUAAUCCCAGCACUUUGGGAGGCCGAGGCAGGCGGAUCACGAGGUCAGGAGAUCGGGACCAUCCUGGCUAACAUGGUGAAACCCCGUCUCUACUAAAAAUACAAAAAAAAAAUUAGCCAGACAUGGUGGCGGGCGCCUGUAGUCCCAGCUACUCAGGAGGCUGCGGCAGGAGAAUGGUGUGAACCCGGGAGGUGGAGUUUGCAGUGAGCUGAGAUCGCGCCACUGCACUCCAGGCUGGGUGACAGAGCGAGACUCCAUCUCAAAAAAUAAAAUAAAAUAAAAUUGGUGAGGUAGUUACAUAGAUAGGGCAGAUUUAGGCACUGAGUUGCUAGAAGCUAUAAUUAGUUGAAAAUGCAUCAGCUAGGAGAGAAAAGCAUUUAAUAUUUGUGUAGAGUAAGAGACCACAAGAAUGCUCAGUAGCAUGUGGAAAUACUUUUAGGAGGUUCAGAGGGGGAAAUGAGGGUAUUAUGGAUGUGGAUUUGCAUGGACAUUUUAGUUGUAGAAUGUUCUGUGGAAAGGGUGGGCUGGACUAAGCCAUGUGAAGAUCUGUUCUUACAUAAUCUACUUUAAUGAUUUCUCCAAAUUUGAGAAACAACUAGCUACCAUGAUACGAGUUCCCAGUAUAUGACACUCAUGACAGGCUUUCACGUAUUUUCCCUGAAUUUUACAACAUAACUCCAGGGUAAGUCUUAUACAGAUUAAAAAACUGAGGUCUAACAAGGUCAAGUUAUUUGAAAGGGAGCAUUGAGUAGUCAGUUACAGGGCUGGUGUUCAGCUUCUGACUGUCUGGCUCUGCCUACUCUGUUAUGCCAGUUUGGGAUGGAAGCCUCCAGAGCAGGCAUUCUCACCUCUACCUAGCACUGUUGGUGCUUUGGGCCCAAUAUGUCUCUGCUGUGGUGGGCAGGUCUGUCUUCUGCACUGUUGGGUGUUGAGAAUAUUCUUGUCCUCAUUCCACCAGAAGCCAGUAGCAUUCUCCUAACUUCCUUUCCAGUUGUGAAAACCAACAGUGUCUCUAGAAGUUGCCAAAUGUAAAUUGUCCCUAGUUGAAAACCUAUGGAGGGCUUUUCAUCCAUUGAAGAGAAUCUCUAAAAUUAACCUUACUUGUUCAGUUAUUUACCUUUAGGAAUACUUGUUUUAAUAUUUUUCGAGACCUUCUUUCUCAGUGAGAACAGACUGAGUCUGCAGAAAUUGAGCCAUGGCCUGUUAUCUUCCUCUCUACCCCAGCUCCAUGUGCAGGAAGCUCUACUCUAAGCCCAUGCAGCCAAAAAGUCAGGGGCUCUGUCUUCCUGCACUUCCUAGGCUAUGGCUGCAGCCCCACCCAGGAGGGGCUGGCCAUGGUUCUUAUUUUCCCCAGACUCAUGUUGCCGAAGCCCAAUUCCUGACAGGCUUGGCCUAGGGCACUAACAUAAAGUAACUUAAAGUGGACUAUAUUCUAGACUCUACCUGGGCUCCUGAGCAUUGUAUCCCAGUGAGUUCCAGCCCCAGCAGCUUGUAAGGCAGAGGUGACAGUGCUGGAGGGGCUACACCACAACCCCAUCCCCAGUGCCCACUUGAUGACCUGAGUAUCCCUCCUGGUAGAGCUGGCUGCUGUCCUGUCCCCAGCUCCAAUGCCAUACUCCAGAGGUUCUGCCCAGGGUGAGAGACAGGUCCUAAGUGCUGAGAUGUCUGCAGCCUUCCCUACAGACUUUGUUUGAAAAAUAGCCUGGCAGAGUUCAUUUCUGAGGAUGUCGUUGAGAACACUGGAGAGCUUGGUGGCCACCAUUUCAGAGGGCAGAAACAGCAACCCAGUCAGAAGCUUCAUGGAGAGUCCUAGAUCCAGCCUAUCCUGGAGCCAGGAGACUGUGAGCAUGUGCUAGGCGCUCUCAGAAGCAGCUGCAAUGGGACUCGGAGCAAAUGUGAAAGGACUCCCUGGGAGAUAACAGCCCUGCAUGAUGCCAGAGCCCACUGACCCAAGGGGCUUACCUACAACCUCUGAGCUGGCCAAAUGAUGCAUGGUCCUCUGUCCCCAAGGUGAGUCCUACAAUGCUGAGCUUACACAUGACAUCACAGGCCUCCCUGUCAGCCUGGAAGAUGGUUUUUGCCCAAGAUGAUGGUCUCAGGAGUCAAUGGAGAAGACCUCCAAGCCACCCAUCCCUGACUGAACACGGGCAAAGUCGUGAAAUCCCUGAAUUGUGAGAGGUCUCUAAGCCACACACAGCCAGUGAUGAAGCUUGGAAGUCCAACUAGCUAAGCCAGCCUGAGCACCACCUUUUGUCACAGGAUCUUUGGGGUGUUGCUUUUCCAGCCACAAACCUCUAUGGCCCGUGGAGCCUUUGUCCAAGUUUUGCUUAGGCCUGCUGGGCUCAUUCUGCCUCCUUGGCCCAGCAGGCUUUGCUUAGCUUGUGCUGCCGGCCCGGAUCCCACGCCUGCCGAGGGUGAGCCCAGAACAGAGUGGCAAGGUGUGUGUGAGCGAGCGUGGGAUCUGGCCACUGCACACAGCCAGGCAUGCUGGCUGUGGCAGGGCAGGCAGCUCCAGGUGCCGGCUCUGUGUGAGGCUGUGGCCAAAUCAGGCGUUCCAUAAGCGACUUCCACUGUGGGCACCAGGAAACGUGGCCCUAGGAGGCUUGGAGACGCUAGGAACCGCAGAUCCCCAAAGAGGAUGUCACAGCCCUGGCUCGGUGAGCUGUUAAGUCUGGGCUCUCUGAAGAGCCACAGAUCUUCUCUCCUUCUCAUUGCUUGCAAUAAGGCGAAUGGCAGGGCGUGUUUCUGCCCUGUUUGUGCUACAGCUCUUUCAUUCCCACCAUUGAGCUGGUCUCAAGUUCUUGUCCGGCAUCCAGGAAGAACAAGGUAUAUGGACAACUAGAGGGUAAGCAAGGCAAAGAGGUGGUUUAUUGAGCGACAGUACAGCUCUCAGGAGACGCUAAGUGGGUAGCUCCUCUCCACAGGCAGGUGGUCCCGAUGAUUGCAGCUCUCAGUGGAGAGGAGACCCGGAGUAGGUAGCUCCUAUCAGCAGGCAGGUCGUUCUGUUGAGUGUGCAGCCCUCAGCGGACAGGGGACCUGGAGUGGGUAGCUUUUCUCCGCAGGCAGGUUGGCUUGUGGAGUGUGCAGCCCUCAGAGUAGAGGGGACCCGGAGUGGGUAGCUCCUUCCCACAGCUGGUAGUCCCAAUUUCUGUGUGAGUCUGGCCGAAACUCGCUUUUUUUAUGAACUUAGAAGGGAGGAAGCGCAUGCUGAUUGGUCCAUGGGCAGCCAUGGGCGGGCCUAGAAAAAGCACUAUCCGAUUGGCUGUAUGGUCAUCAAUGAAGUCCUCACUUCCGGCAGUGGACCUCACUGGGAACUGGCAGCCCGGCCCCGAGGCUUCAGGUUGUUCCUGGCUUGAAGGUUCGUGUUUUAUUCGAACUGAUCAACUAGAUGGUGAAACUGACUGGAAGCUGAAGGUGGCAGUGAGCUGCACGCAACAGCUGCCGGCUCUGGGGGACCUUUUUUCUAUCAGUGCUUAUGUUUAUGCUCAGAAACCACAAAUGGACAUUCACAGUUUCGAAGGCACAUUUACCAGGGAAGACAGUGACCCGCCCAUUCAUGAAAGUCUCAGCAUAGAAAAUACAUUGUGGGCAAGCACCAUUGUUGCAUCAGGUACUGUAAUAGGUGUUGUCAUUUAUACCGGAAAAGAGACUCGAAGUGUAAUGAACACAUCCAAUCCAAAAAAUAAGGUUGGUUUGUUGGACCUUGAACUCAAUCGGCUGACGAAAGCGCUAUUUUUGGCUUUAGUUGCUCUUUCCAUUGUUAUGGUAACCUUACAAGGAUUUGUGGGUCCAUGGUACCGCAAUCUUUUUCGGUUCCUUCUCCUCUUUUCUUACAUCAUUCCCAUAAGUUUGCGUGUGAACUUGGACAUGGGCAAAGCGGUGUAUGGAUGGAUGAUGAUGAAAGAUGAGAACAUCCCUGGCACGGUCGUUCGGACCAGCACUAUCCCAGAGGAACUUGGGCGCCUGGUGUAUUUAUUGACAGACAAAACAGGAACCCUCACCCAGAAUGAAAUGAUAUUUAAGCGGCUGCACCUGGGCACCGUGUCCUAUGGCGCCGACACGAUGGAUGAGAUCCAGAGCCAUGUCAGGGACUCCUACUCACAGAUGCAGUCUCAAGCUGGUGGAAACAAUACUGGUUCAACUCCACUAAGAAAAGCCCAAUCUUCAGCUCCCAAAGUUAGGAAAAGUGUCAGUAGUCGAAUCCAUGAAGCCGUGAAAGCCAUCGUGCUGUGUCACAACGUGACCCCCGUGUAUGAGUCUCGGGCCGGCGUUACUGAGGAGACUGAGUUCGCAGAGGCUGACCAAGACUUCAGUGAUGAGAAUCGCACCUACCAGGCUUCCAGCCCGGAUGAGGUCGCUCUGGUGCAGUGGACAGAGAGUGUGGGCCUCACGCUGGUCAGCAGGGACCUCACCUCCAUGCAGCUGAAGACCCCCAGUGGCCAGGUCCUCAGCUUCUGCAUUCUGCAGCUGUUUCCCUUCACCUCCGAGAGCAAGCGGAUGGGCGUCAUCGUCAGGGAUGAAUCCACGGCAGAAAUCACAUUCUACAUGAAGGGCGCUGACGUGGCCAUGUCUCCUAUCGUGCAGUAUAAUGACUGGCUGGAAGAGGAGUGCGGAAACAUGGCUCGCGAAGGACUGCGGACCCUCGUGGUUGCAAAGAAGGCGUUGACAGAGGAGCAGUACCAGGACUUUGAGCCCAUGCAGUCCAGCUCUGUGGAGUCCACACACAGCACGUACACGUGUGCACACAGGCGCCUCCCCCUCUGUCCCCAGAGCCGAUACACUCAAGCCAAGCUGAGCAUGCACGACAGGUCCCUCAAGGUGGCCGCGGUAGUCGAGAGCCUGGAGAGGGAGAUGGAACUGCUGUGCCUCACCGGCGUGGAGGACCAGCUGCAGGCAGACGUGCGGCCCACGCUGGAGAUGCUGCGCAACGCCGGGAUCAAGAUAUGGAUGCUAACAGGCGAUAAACUCGAGACAGCUACCUGCAUUGCCAAAAGUUCACAUCUCGUGUCUAGAACACAAGAUAUUCAUAUUUUCAGACAGGUAACCAGUCGGGGAGAGGCACAUUUGGAGCUGAAUGCAUUUCGAAGGAAGCAUGAUUGUGCACUAGUCAUAUCUGGGGACUCUCUGGAGGUUUGUCUAAAGUACUACGAGCAUGAAUUUGUGGAGCUGGCCUGCCAGUGCCCUGCCGUGGUUUGCUGCCGCUGCUCACCCACCCAGAAGGCCCGCAUUGUGACACUGCUGCAGCAGCACACAGGGAGACGCACCUGCGCCAUCGGUGAUGGAGGAAAUGAUGUCAGCAUGAUUCAGGCAGCAGACUGUGGGAUUGGGAUUGAGGGAAAGGAGGGUAAACAGGCCUCGCUGGCGGCCGACUUCUCCAUCACGCAGUUCCGGCACAUAGGCAGGCUGCUCAUGGUGCACGGGCGGAACAGCUACAAGAGGUCGGCGGCACUCGGCCAGUUCGUCAUGCACAGGGGCCUUAUCAUCUCCACCAUGCAGGCUGUGUUUUCCUCAGUCUUCUACUUCGCAUCCGUCCCUUUGUAUCAGGGCUUCCUCAUGGUGGGGUAUGCCACCAUAUACACCAUGUUCCCAGUGUUCUCCUUAGUGCUGGACCAGGACGUGAAGCCAGAGAUGGCGAUGCUCUACCCGGAGCUGUACAAGGACCUCACCAAGGGAAGAUCCUUGUCCUUCAAAACCUUCCUCAUCUGGGUUUUAAUAAGUAUUUACCAAGGCGGCAUCCUCAUGUAUGGGGCCCUGGUGCUCUUCGAGUCUGAGUUCGUCCACGUGGUGGCCAUCUCCUUCACCGCACUGAUCCUGACCGAGCUGCUGAUGGUGGCGCUGACCGUCCGCACGUGGCACUGGCUGAUGGUGGUGGCCGAGUUCCUCAGCUUAGGCUGCUACGUGUCCUCACUCGCUUUUCUCAAUGAAUAUUUUGGUAUAGGCAGAGUGUCUUUUGGAGCUUUCUUAGAUGUUGCCUUUAUCACCACCGUGACCUUCCUGUGGAAAGUGUCGGCGAUCACCGUGGUCAGCUGCCUCCCGCUGUAUGUCCUCAAGUACCUGAGGCGCAAGCUCUCUCCUCCCAGCUACUGCAAGCUGGCCUCCUAAGGGGCUGUGCACCCCCAGCGGGCUGGCCCCAGCACCUUCUGCCCUUCCCAGCACCUUGUGCCCUUGCCAGUGAACGCAGGGUUUGCCAUUGCUACCAAGCAAGCACCACAAGAAAGGGAGGGUACGCCAGGCGAGCCCAGGGCACAGAUGCUGAGACAGCCUCUCCUUCUCAGUGCAGGGACGUCACCCCUGCCAGGCAAGCCCAGGGCACAGAUGCCAGGAUGGCUUCUCCCUCUCAGUGCGAGGCUUCACCCCUGCCAGGCAAGCCCAGGGCAUAGAUGCUGAGACAGCCUCUCCCUCUCAGUGCAGGGACGUCACCCCUGCCAGGCAAGCCCAGGGCACAGAGGCCGGGACGGCCUCUCCCUCUCAGUGUGAGGCUUCACCCAUGCUAGGCAAGCCCAGGGCACAGAUGCCGGGAUGGCCCCUCCCUCUCAGUGCGGGAACGUCACCCCUGCCAGGCAAGCCCAGGGCACAGAUGCUGCGAUGGCCUCUUCCUCUUAAGUGUGGGGCCUCACCCCUGCUUUUCUUUCUUUUUUUGUAUUGUCAAAAUUGUAUUUCCAUAUUGAAGCAGCUUGAGUUUCUACUGAAAAUGAGCCCGAAUUAUUUCACUAUUACUGUAAAGGGUUCAUCUUACUCUGGCAUUCUGAGAAUUAGACUGAAAGUUUAAUUUCUGCAGUUCCCUCAUAUUCAGAUUCUUUCUUUGAUGUUAUAACACAAAGUCAUUCCUACUCAAAUGUAAUAAAAUUGAGGCUCCACGGAGGCCCGUGUCCACAUCAGCUGCAGCUCCCACUCAGACAGACGGCCUGCCCCACAGCCUGCCCUUUGCUGAAGAUACCCUCGCUUUAUACUUGCAUUUCGCUUUUCAGUAAAAACAGUCAAGUUACUGAGUUCUCACAUAAA